GCUUUCUGUUGCCGGGCGCAAUGGCGGAUACGCUGGAGUCCUCGCUGGAGGACCCACUGCGGAGCUUUGUGCGAGUUUUGGAGAAGCGGGAUGGUACAGUGCUACGACUACAGCAGUAUAGCUCCGGUGGCGUGGGUUGCGUUGUGUGGGACGCUGCCAUUGUCCUUUCUAAAUACCUGGAAACGCCCGAGUUUUCUGGCGACGGGGCCCACGCGCUGAGCCGGCGGUCGGUGCUGGAGCUGGGUUCGGGCACCGGGGCCGUGGGGCUCAUGGCUGCUACCCUCGGGGCUGAUGUUGUAGUCACCGAUCUUGAGGAAUUGCAAGACUUGCUGAAGAUGAAUAUUAAUAUGAACAAGCAUCUUGUCACUGGUUCUGUUCAAGCCAAGGUACUGAAAUGGGGGGAAGAAAUAGAAGGCUUUCCUUCUCCACCCGACUUCAUACUGAUGGCCGACUGCAUAUACUAUGAAGAGUCUUUGGAGCCAUUGCUGAAAACUCUAAAAGAUAUCAGCGGAUUUGAAACUUGUAUUAUAUGUUGUUAUGAACAACGAACAAUGGGGAAAAAUCCAGAAAUUGAGAAAAAAUAUUUUGAGUGAUCACCCAAACCCUUAUAUGGGCACAAAUCUAUCACAUUGUGAGUGACUCCUUUUGAGGGUACAUCUAUAUAGGCCUGCAGUUUUGUCUGCUGGAAGGACUACUUUGGUUUAAUGAGAAAGCAGGUAUAUGACUGCCUCAGGUAACAAAUACUAAAAUGUUUGUUUAUUUUCAUGUUUUUCUUGAAUAUGAAAAAUGUUCAUGAACUUUUGAAAUGAUGCAUAAUGAAAAUUUCGUACUGUUAAACAGCUUUUAUUGGGGUAAAGCAUAUGUAAAAUGCAUAUGUAUCAGUCAAGUGCUGAGCUUAAUUUUUCAUAUGUAUACACCCAAGUAACUACUUACCAACAUAAAGAUAGAGGACAUUUUCAGGAUCUUGGAAGGUUUGCACACUGCCCUUUCCCAGGCAAUACUCAAAAGGUAACCACUGACCAGGCGCGGUGGCUCACGCCUGUAAUCCCAGCACUUUGGGAGGCCGAGAUGGGCAGAUCAUGAGGUCAGGAGUUCGAGACCAGCCUGGUCAACAUGGUGAAACCCUUUCUUUACUAAAAAUACAAAAAUUAGCUGGGUGUGGUGUCGUUUGCCUGUAAUCCCAGCUACUCAGGAGGCUGAGGCAGGAGAAUCACUUGAACCCAGGGAGGUGGAGGUUGCAGUGAGCCAAGAUCGCACCACUGCACUCCAGCCUGGGUGACAGAGUGAGACUCUCAAAAAAAAAGUAACCAGCAUUCUGACUUCUGUCACCCACAGGUCAGUUCAUAUUAUUGAAUUUGAAGUAUGUCUCUUUUAAAUUUAUAGCUCCUUCAGCUAGAUUUUGACUUUGAAAAAAUUCCUUUGGAAAAACAUGAUGAAGAGUAUCGAAGUGAAGAUAUUCAUAUUAUAUACAUCAGAAAGAAAAAAUCGGUAAAUAACAUUCUCAGUUCUUCAUUCUCCAAGGAGGUUUCAUCAGCUGGACACUAUUUCAGGGCAUAUGUGUGGUAUGGGCGUUGAUUUUGAUGUGGAGAAACAGCUCUAAUGAUUCACUGGACUCAGGCAGUAACUUCAUUGUCAAGAUAAUUUAAUCUAUCUUGCCUUGGGUUUUUGCUCUAAAGCCAGGCUUUUUUUUUUUUUUUUUUUUUUUUUCUCGUAUUUUUUAAGUAGAGACACGUUUCACCGUGUUGCCUAGACUGGUGUCGAACUCCUGGGCUCAAGUGAUCCGCCCACUUCGGCCUCCCAAAGUUCUGAGAUUACAGGCAUCAGCCACCAUACCUGGCCAGGCUUCGCUUUUAAAGGCCUUUUCCAGCUUCUCCAUAGGCGUAAAUUGUAUAGCUCUAUAAUUGGGUAUUACCUCAGACAAGUUAUUAGCUAUUUAUAAGUUUCUUUUAUCUCUGUGAGAUUUUAAAAUGCCUGCUCUUACCUUUGUGAACUUUUCCUUAUUAAAAAUUGUUUACAGGAAAUGAAAUACAACAAGGCAGAUGAGUCCAUAAAAGAUAAAUGCACUCAAUUAAGUAGAAUUUAUGUAUUUUCCCGCUUCUUGGUGCAUGUUUUACCCUGUAUAACAAUCACAUUUUAUGCAGGUUGCCUCAGUGACACCUAGGGUUUGAGCCUGUAGAAAGAGGGAAGAAUUGUACUUCAUCCUUUUUUUUUUUUGAAAUAGGGUCUCACUCUGUCAUCCAGGCUGGAGUACAGUGGUGCAAUCUCGGCUUGCUGCAGCCUCUGCCUUGCAGGCUCAAGAAGUGAUCCUCCCACCUCAGCCUCCUGAGUACCUGGGACCAUAGGCAUGCACCACCAUGCCCAGCUAAUUUUUGUAUUUUUUUUGUUGUUGUUGAGACAGGGUUUUGCCAUGUUGUCCAGGCUGAUUUUGCACUCCUGGACUCCAGUGACCUGCCCACCUCGGCCUCCCAAAUUGUUGGGAUUACAGGUGUGAGCUGCUGCGCCUGGCCUUUCAUCUAUUUUUGUAUUUCCAGCACCUUUGGUAUAUGUGACUAGUGUAAGGCAGGGAGAUGAUUAGUUUUAUGAAUUAAGGAUGCUAGAUUCAAUAAGCCCACACUUUUUCUAUCAUCUUUGCUUUGAUUAUGUUUGUGGUAAAGUUUUCUGAUUAUAUGAAUUCUAGUCAAAAGCAAAUAAAACUUAGGGAACAGAAGUAGGUGUUAGGACUAAAUCUAAGUAAAAAGGCAGCAGCGGGAUUAUUCAGAUUAACAUUUAUGUGGCAUGGUGCCACAGAUACAAAAAAAACUGUUUUGUGCUUUAAGGGAUCUAGUGUUAACUGAAGCUGUUGUGCAGUUUUAAAAGUAGAAUUUUUUGGAGGCAGAAAGAUUUUGUGUUUCCUAAAUAUAGAGGCUUUUUUUUUUUUUUCGGCCAAAAAAAAAAACUCUUAUUUUUUAGUUGAUGUAACUCACAUACCAUAAAAUUCACGCUUUUAAGGUGUACAAUUUGGUGGUUUUUAGUAUAUUCACAUAGUUGUGUAAAUUACCACUUUCUAAUUUUUAAUGAUUUCACCCCCCAGAGAAGCCUCUUACCCAUUAGCAGUCACUCCCUGUUACCCCCGUCCCCAGCUGCUGGCAGCCACUAAUCUCUAUGGAUUUGCCUAUUCUGCACAUGUCAUAUGUAACAAGUCACAUACUGUGUGGCCUCUUGUGACUGUCUUCUUUCACUCAGCACAGUAUUCUCGAGCCUUAUCUACAUUGUAGCACACAUUAGCACUUAACUCCUUUUUGUGGCUGAAUAAUAUUCCUUUAUGUGGCUGUACCACACCUUAUCCAUCCAUUGAUGAGAUGAAUAAUGCUGCUAUGGACGUUCAUCUACAAAUUUUUGUGUGAACAUGUUUUCAGACCUCUUGAGUAUAUACCUAGAGGAGAACUGCAAGGUUAUAUGGGAACUCUGUUUAACUUUUUGAAGACUUGCCAAACUGUGUUCCUAAUCUACCAUACCAUUAUACGUUCUCACUAGCAGUGUAUAAGGGUUCCAGUUUUCUCCACAUUUUUACCAACAUUUGUUAAUUAUACCCAUCUCACUGGGUAUGAGAUAGUCUCUAAACUGUGGUUUUCAUUUCUCUAAUGACUAAUGAUGUUGGGUAUCUUUUCUGUAUUUAGAAGAAAUGCUUGGCCCAUUUUCAGAUUGACUUAUUUGUCUUUUUACUUUGAGUUGUGAGAGUUCCUUAUACAUUCUGAAUACUAAACACUUACAGAUGCAUUAUUUGUGAAUAUUUUCUCCCAUUCUGUGGGUUGUCUUUUCAUUUUCUCAAUAGUGUGUCUUGUAUUUUCUUAAUUUAUUAUUUUCUUAUUUUUCUUUUGAGACAGAGUCUCGCACUGUCACCCAGUCUGGAGUGCAGUGGCAUGAUCUUGGCUCAGUGCAACCUCUGCCUCCCAGGUUCAAGUGAUUCUCCUGUGUGAGCCUCCCAAGUAGCUAGGACUAAAGGCAUGUGCCACGACGCCCAGCUAAUUUUUUUGUAUUUUUAGUAGAGAUUGGGUUUCACUAGGUUGGCCAGGCUUGUGUCGAACUCCUGGCCUCAAGUGCUCUGCCACCUCAGCCUCCCAAAGUGCUGGGAUUACAGGUGUGAGCCACCACACCCGGCCUAUGUUGUGUCUUUUGAAGCACAUAUAUUUUAAUUUUGAUAAUGUCCAAUGCAUCUGUUCUUUCUUCAGUUGCUUGUUAGGUGUCAGCAAAGAACCAUCUAUAAACAUGCAUGGUUGUUCACUUGAAUUGCAUGUAGCCACUGUUAUACUAGGCAUACUAGGCAUUAUGAGGCAUAUUAGGCAUUAUUAAAUACCCAGUAAAUAGUUUGUGGUAAAUCAAUCUUUUAAGUUUCCUUUUUUUUUGUUAUAGAAAUUUCCAUCGUGAAGCCUUUAAUCAUCUUACCCAAGGCUCUAACAACCUGGGUAAACUAAAGAUGUGAAUAGAGCAUGUGAAUACAGCAUGGGAAGAUUGUGUUCACAGAUUUUUUUUUCCGGCACGUCCUUAGAGAUCCGAUGUAUAGAUGAUGACCACCAGGGGCUGUCUGCAAUACGAAAAAUUCCUGCUUGCCUGCCUGCCUGCCAAUGGCCCUGAAUCCAGCUUAGGUUACUUAGUUCAGCAUCAAGUUCUUCUUAAAUGUUGGGAAUCAGUUAUUCAAAUAAAAAUUGGUAUUGAGGCGAGGCUGAAAUCUGCCAAAAACAGCCAACAUGAUUUGACUGGACCUUUUACAGGAAGCUAGAGAUAAAUUUCUGAAGAGAACUAUCUGCUAUUAUAUAAUAAUGUUUUAAAUUCAAACUAGUAAAUUUUAGUUUGUCUUCAGAGUUUAAAAGGUUUUCAUUUUGUACAUAAUUAUACAAUAUUUAUCAUUUGUAUUUUCCACUUCAUUUCUUUUAAAAUAUCUUUAAUACUGAAAUGUUCUUUUAAUUUUAAAAAGAACUGAGAUAUUGUCUUGUAUACUUAUAUUAGCCAAAGUUUUCUUUUCCUCCACCAUACAUAUCUAUGUGAUUUAAUCAGUAAAUUGUACUGUAAUGAGUUGCUAAGAAGACAAAUCAGAAGAUUGGAGGAACAAAAGAUAUCUUUACAGAUUUUUCAUUUGAGCAUGGAGUGAGAAUAGAAAGACCAGUUUCAGGCUUAUGCACUUACGUGGCUCAUGCACUUUAUGUAUAUGUUCCAGGAAAAUCUGGCUUAAAAAUACUGGUAUUGUUUACAUGAAGCAGUGAAAGGUUUUUGAAUAACUACAAAUGUAGUUCUAUAUGUAUAUACCAAAUGAAUUUCUGUUCUGUGUCUCUCUGUUUUAUGUUAUGAAGCCAUUCGCUCAUAUACAAUAAUCUGUCAAGGACUUUAAUCAUACUUGUUCCAAAGAGUAGUAACCGGAUGGAAUUCUGGUAUUUAUAGGCAUUGGUGCUAGAUGGUACAUUUUAUGUGUUAAAAUAAACAUUGUUUUUGAGA